AGUCUCGGGCGGCGGUGUCCGGCGCGCGGGCGGCCUGCUGGGCGGGCUGAAGGGUUAGCGGAGCACGGGCAAGGCGGAGAGUGACGGAGUCGGCGAGCCCCCGCGGCGACAGGUUCUCUACUUAAAAGACAAUGACUACUGAUGAAGGUGCCAAGAACAAUGAAGAAAGCCCCACAGCCACUGUUGCUGAGCAGGGAGAGGAUAUUACCUCCAAAAAAGACAGGGGAGUAUUAAAGAUUGUCAAAAGAGUGGGGAAUGGUGAGGAAACGCCGAUGAUUGGAGACAAAGUUUAUGUCCAUUACAAAGGAAAAUUGUCAAAUGGAAAGAAGUUUGAUUCCAGUCAUGAUAGAAAUGAACCAUUUGUCUUUAGUCUUGGCAAAGGCCAAGUCAUCAAGGCAUGGGACAUUGGGGUGGCUACCAUGAAGAAAGGAGAGAUAUGCCAUUUACUGUGCAAACCAGAAUAUGCAUAUGGCUCGGCUGGCAGUCUCCCUAAAAUUCCCUCGAAUGCAACUCUCUUUUUUGAGAUUGAGCUCCUUGAUUUCAAAGGAGAGGAUUUAUUUGAAGAUGGAGGCAUUAUCCGGAGAACCAAACGGAAAGGAGAGGGAUAUUCAAAUCCAAACGAAGGAGCAACAGUAGAAAUCCACCUGGAAGGCCGCUGUGGUGGAAGGAUGUUUGACUGCAGAGAUGUGGCAUUCACUGUGGGCGAAGGAGAAGACCACGACAUUCCAAUUGGAAUUGACAAAGCUCUGGAGAAAAUGCAGCGGGAAGAACAAUGUAUUUUAUAUCUUGGACCAAGGCCAAAGAAUCCUGGGAGAUGGAUACCAAAGAAAAAUUGGAGCAGGCUGCCAUUGUCAAAGAGAAGGGAACCGUAUACUUCAAGGUGUGUGAGUCCCUAUGCAAUCCUUUCCAUCUCAAAGAAUUUAUUCAAGUGUUGGUGAAUUGUGCUGAUAUUCCCUACUCUGAAUUUUGUCAACACUGCUUGGUAAGAAUAAGCUGCAAUUUUUAUAAAUCUGUCAUUUUCAAUAUGAAAAAUGGUGAGAAAACAAUCAUGUGGAAAAAAAAAAAAGUACAGAUUCCUCUUUUACACAUUCUGCUCUAGAUUGUAACCUUCCAUACAGGCAGACCAGGUCUGGCAUCCCCACCCACCACAGUAUCACUCACUCCUAAAGCAUCUUGCUUGGUACAUAGUUGGCACUCAACAAGUGUUUUUGGAAUGAAAAAAGAAUGAAUAGAAUAAUUGUUAGCAAAGAAUGGAAUUCAUAAGGGUAAGUUUCACAUCAUUUUUCUUUCUUCCUUUUUUUUUUUUUGUAUGAGAGACAGGGUCUCCCUUUCUUUCCCAGGCUGGUCUCAAACUUCUAGCCUCAAGCAAUCCUCCCACCUCAGCUUCCCAAAGUGCUGAGAUUACAGGCGUGAGCCACUGCACCGGGCCCAUCUUCCUUUAGACUGUCUUGAUGAAGUCACUAGAGCAUAUGAUAAAAGGAGAGAGGACAUGCACAAAUUUCAAAACAAACUGACAGGAGAGUAUUGAUUGCUUCUAAUGGCCAAGAUGAUUCCUGCACACUUGCUUUUAUGAGGAAUCUCCGGAUAUUCCUGAAUGAUAUUCAUCAUAAAUUGCUUCUCAGAAACCCUUCUUGGAGCAACUAGGAGUGUGAUAUUUUCUCACUUAGAUCUUAAACCUCUAGAUGUAAGAAAAAAAGAAACCGCCCUUCAUUCUGUUUUAAUCAGUGUUCUACCCAUUGCUUCCCCACCCCAAAUAUAUGCCUUCUCCAUGUCAAGCAGAAAGGGCUUAGUGAUGAGAAUUAGAGGGAGAAUGGGAGUUCUGUCAAGGUUUCUUUCGUUUUCUGCCACUGCAAUACAGAAAUUAGAUGUUUUUCAGCAGUAUAAAGCAGUGAGGCAUAAGUGUACUUUAACAAGUCUUUAUGGGGCAUCUGCUAUAAGACAUGCUAUUAUUAAGUUACAACCUUGUCAGGAGGGAGGAGUGGCAAUGUUAAUCCAAAUGAAACAACUAGAGAAUUAUGUAAGAAUAUAUAAUCAACCCAAAAUUAACACAGCCAGAGGGCACCAUGUGUUUUCAGAAUUUGAGCUGAGACAAUAUUGGGUCAUGAAAUCAGUUUUGUGGAAGUGUAUUGCAAUAUGUUAUAAGGAUCAGUUUUGUUGCAUAAAACUUUGCUUGUGUAUGAGUAAGUACUGGAUUGCAUAUUUCUUACUGUGGGUGGUAUUCAAACAAAUUUUAAAUCAUGGGUUUAGAUAAGUAUAAAUAUAUAAAUAUGUUAUUUAUCAUUAUUUACUAUGUAUACUAAACUCUUAUGGAUCACCAGAAAGCAUGGGGGUAUGAUAGAAUAAGCUCAGAAUUGGGAAAAAUGGGCUUUAUUGCUCUUCAAAUGAUUUAGUCAUUUAAGGUCCAAAGAGGUUAUAUUUUCAAGUGAAAAAUAGGGGAGUUAGAUGUUCCCCAAGUUUCUUUCCAGCCUGAAUUUCUGUGAGUUUCUAAACUCUCAAGAACAAGUGUUAUUUUUUUGGUUUUGUUUUGUUUUUAAUUCUAAUUGAGGUAUAUUGGAUACUUCUAAACUAUUCAAGUAAGAUUCCAAGUGGGUUAUUUGUAUAUCCAAAUACAUAAUACACUAGAGGGAAAAAUGUUUCUACAAAAUUUCUUAAGAUCGUGAGUCCUUAACAGUAUUUUCUAUAUUUCCGAAGUCCAUAAAAAUCCUUAACUAUAUUUUAUAUAUUUCCUCAAUACUUCCAAAUAGAAUAUUAACAGUUUGGGAAGAUUUGAGGCUUUUGGCCUUUGACUAGAAUUAUAUCGAUUCAGUGUAGUAAAACAGCUCAGCUAUUCAGAGGCUCUAAUCGGUGCUAUGAUACAGAAUUUUGGAGAACAUUAUUGGUAAUGAAAUAAUGUUAUGAAGCCAUCUGUCAUAUAGCUGUGUUCUGAAUAUAUACAGAGAGAUGGCCAGAAUUAGUGAUCAGUAGCAGAAAGCAAUGAGUGUCUGUACAGUUACUUAACUUUGUUGCUUAUCAGCAUCACAACUGCAAGAGUGAUACUAUUAUGAACCUACUUAAAAUUACCAAUCUUUGGAUAAAAUCUGGAUCAGCAGUCACACACAUGGAAAAAAUUAUUUUUAACAUGGAAUUUGAUAGGCAAAAUUUUUCAAAACAUUAGUCCAUUGGGGAAAAAUUAAUGAAAGGUUCAAAACCACUGACCUGAGACUUUUCUCCCAGAAUGUCUCUGAACAUUUUGUACCACUAAAAACUUCCCUGGAGGCACCUUUAUAAUUAUAGGUAAAAGAUCCCAGCAGUAGUCCUAGCGUUAGCUGUAAAACUUCAAAAUGGUUAGUAGAUAGUUUCCUGUACAUAUUCCCUUCCCAACUCAGGGCAGGUUUCAAUCUGCCAUACUGCCCUCCCGGGCCUUGUCUUUCCAGGGUGUCUGACUUGGCAUGUUAUGCAUUUGCACAGAGUCCAGAUGUGUAGGUGAGAGCAGAGAUGGGCUGAACUAAAGAUCUGUAUUUCAUGCCAUCUGCAUAUUGGAAUUCUGUUUCCAUUGAUCUGUUGGUUUGGUUUAUACCUAAAUGGGUAAAGCCUCUCUCCUGAGUAGGAUUGAAUUGUACUCAGCUUUUAAGUGGGAAUGAUUUUGCCAUUGAAGAUGUAAAGUCCUCAUUUCAACCUCUGAAUACUAAAGAGAAGAAAAAUAGAGAACUCUAUUUGGCUCUGAAAAUAAUUAUUAAGUACAGGUAACAGCAUAAUAUUAAGCCAGGCAUUGUGCAAGCGAGUUAAACAGACACGAUUUUUGCCCUCAUAGCUGACAGUGUUCUGCAGGACAGGAGCAUUAACUCACACCUGGUCAGUGUUUUUCUUUUUUCUGACUUGGCAGCAGAGUGGCAAGAAGGCUAAGAACACUGAAGUGAUGUGGGAUUCUUGCGCCCCCUUGUGCUUCUCCUGGGAAGAAAGCAUUUCUAAAACAAACUAGUUGAGGAGAAUUGUUCAACCUCUAAACUCUUCAGAUAAAUCGGGCUUUGCUAUAUUUUCACCACCCUUGCUGUUCCAAGAUACCAGUAAUGUGAUUUAGAAACAAGCCGUUUAUGACUCUAGGAUUUGAUGUUUUAAAAAAAAUUCCUAAGAAGAGUCCACCCUGUCUUUCAUCUCUUUCCUUUAGUGCAGAAUUUUUCAACCUCAGUACUAUCAACAUUUGGAGUGGGAUAAUUCUUGAUUGUGUGGGGCUGUCUUGUGCAUUGUAGAAUAUUUAGCAGCAUUCCUGGCCUCUGCCCAUUAGAUGCCAGUAGCAUCCUACCCAGUUAUGACAACUAAAAAUGCCUCCAGACCUGCCAGGUGUUCCCUGGGGGGCAAAAUCACCCCCCAGUUGAGAACUGCUUUAGUACCUCAGAAGCAGGGAGUACAAGACAGACUUUUCGCUAAUUGGAAGUUGAAGUCUAAAUAAAGUUACAUGAUAUAUAUGCAAGAGCUUUCAAAAAAUUAAAAUGCCCUAUGUGAAGGAACUAUUAAGAAGUCUAAUACCUGUUUUUUGUGUUUUGUUUUGUUUUACCAUGGCCUUCUACCAUUCUGAUUAUUCAGAACUUAUUGAAAUGUUAAGAUCUAGGUUUUUGUCCUCCCUGGCUCUUCUUUUCUUUCCCUAUACAAUAUAUUAGGAGAUAAUCAGAAAAGUUAAGUUAAUCAAUGCAUUAGAGAGGGAGGAGGAGAGAGGAUGAAGAAAUGAGGCAUGACAGGGGAAAUGCCUGUCCUUCCUAUCUCAUCUCAGUGAAACAACACUUUUCAUUUCCACCCACACAUUUUUUGCUCCCAAUGAUAGCAAAAGGUUUUGUUGUUGGUAUUGUUUUUAGAGAGAGAGGGUCUUACUCUGUCACCCAGGCUGGAGUGCAGUGGCACAAGCAUAGCUAACUGCAGCUUCGAACUCCUGGACUUAAGAGAUCCUCCUGCCUCAGCUUCCCAAAGUGCUGGGACUAUAGGCGUGAGCCACCACACCACUUUAGAAAAAGUCUUGAUUCCAUAUUUACAUUCCUUUGAUUUCAAUAUUUACUCAACAAACCUUUAUUAAAGACCUCUUGGUGCUAAACCCUGAAUAUUCCAAAAGGGAGAGGACAAUGCUGCCUGUCCUCAAAGACCAGCAAGAGAAAAGGCAGUGACAGAAAGAAAAUGCCGACCUGAAACUGGUGAGGACUUUAUUCUUUUUUUUUUGUAGCAUCCAAAAAAGGAGUGGUAGGCCUAAGACUAUGACAAAAUUUAAGUAUUGUCUUAGCUUGGGCUGCCACAGUAAAAUACCAUACACUGGGUGGCUUCAACAACAGGAAUUUACUUCUGGAGACUGUAAGUCCCAGAUCAAGGUGUUAGCAGGAUCAGUGUCUGGGGAGGGCCUCUCCUCUGGUUCCUUGUAGCUCCCUUCUUGCUGUGUUCUCACAUGGCCUUUCCACAUGCAUGUGAGUGGAGAGAGGGCAGAGGGCAGCAAGCACCCGAGUUUCUUCUUAUAAAGGCUCUAAUCCCAUCAUGAGGCCCCACCCUCAUGACCACAUCUAACCUAAUUCCCUCCCCAAAUGCUCCAUCUGCAAAUAUCACAUUCGGGGUGAGGGCUUCAACAUAGGAAUUUAGGAUGGGGGACACAAUUCAGUCCAUAGCAAAUCUAAUUUCCUCAAGAAUUUCAGCAUUUAAAAUAAAAUGCCCUGGUUUCGUGUUCUUAUGAAUGACCUGUAUCACACACUUCUGAGGCAGAGAGGGUGACAGACUUUGAUUUUAGUGCCAGUCUUCCCUCUCCUAAGUGAGUGACUUGGGAAGAAGGAUGUUCGAGGGAUGUAGCCUGGCCCUCAUUCACACCCAGGCCCUCCAGCUGGAACAGGUCUGCCCCAUCUUCAUCACCAGAAAAUCCACACCAGGGCUUCCUUUCUACAGGCAGAGCUCGUUUCUUACAUCACCCACUUGAAGUCCUGUAUCACAGGCAUGUCCUCUUAGACCUGCUCUAUGGUUUUUCUCUUACUCAGACUCCUUGGGUGAGGGUUGGAGUAUUUGUGGGGAGAGACAACUCGGCAGUGAGAUGUACGCGCUGCUUGGGCUGUGGUAAAUCCUAGUAACAUGGUCUUAACACUGUUGGUCAGGCAUUGAAUUUAAUGUCCUAAUAGGUCUGGCUGCUCCUCUGCCAUCUGGCAGGAUGUAUCAUCUGUGGUUUUGAGCUUAUCACCUCCUCAAAGGAGAAUCCCCACUUGUACUCCUGUUUCUAUUUGCGUAUUUACCAGCGAUUCCCCAGUGCUUUCAUUUACCUUAAAAUCACAGUGGACACAUUGUCUCAGCCCUGGAGGGGUUUUGUUUUGUUUUGUUUUGUUUUGUUUUGUUUUUGAGGAGUCUCGCUCUGUCACCCAGGCUGGAGUGCAGUGGCAUGAUCUUGGCUCACUGCAACCUCUGCCUCUUAGGUUCAAGCAGUUCUCCUGCCUCAGCCUCCUAAGUAGCCGGGAUUACAGGCAUAUGCCACCAUGCCUGGCUCAUUUUUGUAUUUUUAGUAGAGACGGCCAGGCUGGUCUCGAACUCCUGACCUCAGGUGAUCCACCUGUCUCGGCCUCCAAAGUGCUGGGAUUACAGGUAUGAGCCACUGUGCUCAGCCCCCAGCGUUUCUCAUAUGAGCAUGUAUAUAUAUAUAUAUUAUAUAUAUAUUAUAUAUGUUUAUAUUUAUAUAUAUUAUAUAUAACUGACAGACCUUUCUGAUGUAUAUUGUUUUAUAGUUGUUAUUUAUGUUGUAUGCUACUAUCCAACUAUUCAUAUUCCCAUUGCCUAUAGAUCAGGGGUCAGCAAACUACAGUUUGCUGGCCAAAUCUGGUCCCUGCCUGUUUUUGUAAGUACAGUUUAACUGAAACACAGCUGCACCCAUUGAUUUACAUACUGUCUAGAGCAGCUUUUGCACUACAAAUGAUAAGAAUUUAGUAGUUGCAACAGAGACUGGUUCAAAUAGGAUUGGCUGUGUUUGGAACUAGCACUUGCCAGAAUGUAAUAUUUGCUGUGAAGUGCUGAAAAGAAAAGUAACUUCCUUUUCAUUUUUUUAGUGGCAUAGUCUAAAACUGCUCACAAUCCUUUUGAAAGACUAAAGAAUAGGCCAGGUGUGGUGGCUCAUGCCUGUAAUCCCAGCACUUUGGGAGGCCAAGGCAGGCGGAUCACAAGGUCAGGAGUUCAAGACCAGCCUGGCCAACAUAGUGAAACGCUGUCUCUACUAAAAAUACAAAAAAAAAUAGCUGGGCUUGGUGGCGGCCACCUGUAGUCCCCAGCUACUCGGGAGGCUGAGGCAGGAGAAUCGCUGGAACCCGGGAGGCGGAGGUUGCAGUGAGCUGAGAUGGCGCCAUUGCACUCCAGCCCUGGAGACAGUGCGAGACUGUGUCUC